GUGGAGGGUGACGCCAUGGGUGGGGCGGAGCGUCUGGGAUGCGCUGGGAGCCUAGGAUCCCCGACAGUUUUGCAGAACACUGAAAUCUAUGGACUCUAAAAUGGACUUCAUUUAAAGAAACCCACGGACCAUUAAUGGACAAAAACAUGAGUCAAUAUGUAUUGUGGCAUUCAAAUCCUAGCACUCUGGGAGAGCAUCAAGUACCACGUUUUUGAAGACCAUGGCCUAUCAUCAUUAUGCAUUCAAGAUUUGAGUUUGAAUAACCUCAUCAAGACUUAGAUCUUCUUCAGAAGCUUCAAGUCUCAUCUGCAUUAAAGCUCUCCAUUGAACCCUCUCACAAAAGUACAAGCUUAAAGGGGCUAAAAUCCAUUAAUACAUUCCAUUUUAUAUCCCUUCCUCUGACUUCUCUUCAAUUUCCUUGGCCUCUAGGGUCCUUCAUAUUGCUUACGUUCCUUUAGACUAGAGCCAAGGAGACAGUGCUUUCCAAAAAAAAAAAAAAAAAAAAUGUGUUCUGUGGCCAUAAGUUUUCAUUGAUAGAGAAGCAUAAAUUUGGUGAAUUUAGAAUUAGGUCUUUUAUCAUAUCCUAUAAAAAGUUGAGUUAACAGGCUGGGCACGGUGGCUCAUGCCUGUAAUCCCAGCACUUUGGGAGGCCAAGGCAGCUGGAUGCCCCAAGGUCAGGCAUUUGAGACCAGCCUGGCCAACAUGGCGAAACCCCAUCUCUACUAAAAAUACAAAAAUUAGCCAGGCAUGGUGGCAGGCGCCUGUAAUCCCAGCUACUCGAGAGACUGAGGCAGGAGAAUCACUUGAAACCAGGAGGCGGGGGCUGCAGUGAGCCAAGAUCACGCCACUGCAUUCCAGCCUGGGUGACAGAGCGAGACUCCGUCUAAAAAAAAAAAAAAAGUUGAAUUAACAAUAAGGAAAUGAGGAUGAAGCGGUAAAAAUGUUUUGGGUUACAUUAUACUCUCAGAAGCUAUGUGGUUUAGAGAAAAGGGCCCCCAACCACAAAAGUUAGUGGUUCUUAUUCUGUCUGCUUCGUACUAGGUAUAUGGUAACUGAGAAAGUCACUUAACCUCUCUGAACCUUAACUUCGUCAUCUAUAAAGUGAAUCUAACAUUUUCCCCCCGGCCUACCUCACAGGGUUGUUGUGAGGAUCAAAUGAAAUAAUGUACAUGAAAAGACAUAUAUAAAAUGUAUAAUACAGACAAAGGGUCCUGUUACACAGUUGGAAGUCAUUCCCUCAGAUUUUGGGCCUAGGAAGGUAGGUGAUUUAAACUCACUGAAAGCAUGUACCAUGUCCAGGUUGGAUACAUGGCAACAAGGCUAUGUUAAAUUUUUUUUCUCUGAGUUGAGUCCCUAAAAUACUAUCAUGGGCUAAUUCUAAGAAGGAGCACGAAUAUAUAUUCCCCUAAAAUUAUAGCUUAGCAUUGUCAAUGCUUUAGAGCAGUUAUGGGAGUUAUAGAUUAUAACAUAUUAGUGAUUUGUGAAACUUUUUUACUAAAAUGUGACCCUCAUUUUUCUUUACAUGAAAGAACAUAGAAUAUUUCACAAUGCAUCCCACGUGGUAAGAAUAAAAAAUUGUUUUAGUUAUAUGUACAAAUGUGUGUGUGUGAACGUGUGUGUACUUGGUCAUUAAAUAAAAUGUACUUUUUUUUUUCCUGUGAGUUGCACUUGCUGUUCUUUCUUUCUUUUCCUUUUCCUUUUUCUUUUUCUUUUUUUUGAGACAGAGUCUGGCUCUGUCACCCAGGCUGGAGUGUAGUGGCGCAAUCUUGGUUCACUGCAACCUCUGCCUCCUGGGUUCAAGCGAUUCUCCUGCCUCAGCCUCCCGAGUAGCUGGGACUACAGGCACUCGCCACUGCGCCUGGCUAAUUUUUAUAUUUUUAGUAGAGAUGGGGUUUCGCCAUGUUGGCCAGGCUGGUCUCAAAUUCCUGACCUCAGGUGAUCUACCUGCCUCAGCCUCCCUGGGAUUACAGGCGUGAGCCACCAUGCCUGGCCUCUUUUUCUUUUUGAGACAGGGUCUCACUUUAUCACCCAGGCUGGAGUGCAAUGGCACAGGCUACAGCAGCGGCAUGAUCAUGGCUCACUUCAGCCUUGACCCACCAGGCUCAAGUGGUCCUCUCACCUCAGCCUCCCCAGGUAGCUGGGACUACAGGCACAUGCCACCACACCCAGCUAAUUUUUGUAUUUUUUGUAGAGAUGGGGUUUCAUCAUGUUACCCAGGCUGGUCUUGAACUCCUGAGCUCAAGCGAUCCACCCGCCUUGGCCUCCCAAAGUGCUGGGAUUACAGACAUGAGCCACUGUGCCCGCCCAUCAGUUGCUGUUCUUGGAGUACCAUUUUGGCACUAAUGCCUUCCUACACAUUUGGAUUCCUAGGAGACUCAGCAUUUUUUUUCACUUUAUGCUACUACUCGUGACAAAGAAUUUAAUAUCAAUUUGACUUAUGGUGUAAUUGAAAUAUUUUUUAUUUUGUAGCACAGAGAAAGCCUAUAUGCCUUAUGGAUAUUUAAUAUUUUAAUAUCUAUUCUGAUAAUAGCAUUUAAAAGGUUGCUUCAACCUCUACUAGCAGAAGGAUUGUGUCAAAUAUUUUGCUUUUUAAUUUUUUUUUACUUGUAUCUUUCUGGCCUAAUGGCAAACAAAACCCUCCUUUUAGCAUUACUUGAGGACUAAGUAGAGAGAGGCUAUCGAGAAUGUAGUUAGCAUGACUGGGAAUUUGAUGGUCUCUGGAAAAGAAAAUGCCAUUUCUUUUCUUUCUCUGAGUAACUAGGUUUAUCUUUAGUUUAAUGAUUUAAGAUAAAUAAGUCACUGACAUUAACUUGUUCAACUGUUACUCCUAAAAAUAGAUAUCUCCCUCUUUGAUGAUAGCAUUGGUUAGGUUAGCAUAGGUGACUUUAUUAUAGUGUCCGUGAACAAUAGGGCAUGGUUGUGCUUUCCAAUUCAUUGAUGAAGAACUAAUUUUUUAGUGCUUUAGUGUACUGAAAUGCUGUCUUUAGUGCCCUGGAAUUACUUAUUUAAACUGUGAUAGAAGGUUGUACAAGGUAUUACUUUUCUCUGCUUAUAAAUUAUAUGAAUGUACAUAGUCCUAGCAAUAUGAAUAUUUAUCAGAAGAUGUAUAAUGUAGAAUCCAACUGCCUCAUUCUUCCUGAACAGCCAUGGCCAAACUUCUUGCAUUAAUGGAGACAGAAUGAAUUGCAAAGGUUGUAUAAAUCGAGGCUGUUAUGUUUAUGACAAUUGGCAGCUGUGGCAUAAAAGGCUCAUUACUAUAUGUAAUUGACAUUUUGUUGUUCCUUCUUCCUCCACUCCUUUGCCAAAAAAUGGCAUUGGUAUUACUACCUCUCCAUGUAGGAAGUAGGAUCUACCUAUGAGAAAGUUCAAGAGAGUAGUUAAGCAACUUCAGCUAUCCCUGACCUUCUUCCACAACCCUCAUGAAACUAAUCCAUUGCAAAAUUCUGUCUUUUCUACUUCCUAAAUAUCUUUCAAAUUAUUCACCUGUUUCCAUGUCCAUCCUUAUUUAUUUUAUCAUCUUCGCCUACAUUUUUGCAAUAACUCUUCAAUGGUUUUUUGUAUUUACUCCUCCCCCCUCUAAUCUCAUUGCUUUUAGACUGAUUUUUAAAAAUACAAUUCUAAUCUUUUUGGUCCUCCAAUCUAAACUCUUAUUAUCUUAUUGCCCUUAGAAUUCAGCCCCAAAUCUUCAAUCAUUCUUUGUCUACUAAGCUCAAGCCAUAAUGGUCUUCCAAUUCUCUGACAAUGCCAUUUUUUUUUCUUCAGGGUAUUUGUUGUUGUUUUUGUUGUUGUUGUUGUUGUUGUUUUUGAGACGGAGUUUUGCUCUGUCGCCCAGGCUGGAGUGCAGUGGUGCAAUCUUGGCUCACUGCAACCUCCGCCUCCCAGGUUCAAGCAGUUCUCUGCCUCUGCCUCCCAAGUAGCUGGGAUUAUAGGCGCCCGCCACUAUGCCUGGCUAAUUUUUGUAUUUUUAGUAGAGAUGGGGUUUCACCAUGUGGGCCAGGCUGGUCUUGAACUCCUGACCUCGUGAUCCACCCACCUGGGCCUCCCAAAGUGCUGGGAUUACAGGCGUAAGCCACAGCGCCCAGCCUUCUUUAGGGCUUUUGCAGAGCAGAUACUUUCUGCUUGGAAUGCCCUCCUCUCUCCUGUUCCUCUUCACAUAACCCACUUCUACUCAUACUACCAGUCUCACUUUAAAUAUUAUUUUUUCCAAGAAGCCUUCCUCCAUAUCUCAGACUAGAUUAGACCUCCCUUCUCUAUCAUUCUGUCAUAAAUCACCCAUUUUUUUCUCACAUCUAGCAUAGUUGUAAUUAUUUCUCAUAUAUAAUCAUUUAUUAAUAAUCUUACAAGACAACCUUCAGGAGGGCAAUGACUGGUGCAUGUUUUAUUACACUGUAUGCCCAGUGUUUAGGAAAUUUCCUGGCAAAUAGUAGGGAUUCAGUAAAUAUUUGUCAACUGAUUCUUCCCACAGCCACCACUCUUCACUUAGAUAUUUCAGUACUGUAAGUUCUGGGUUGUUUAACUUCCUCUGUUCAAAACCCUCCUCUUGACUGACUGCAGUGCUCACGACUGCAAUUCCAGCACUUUCGGAGGCCAAGGCAGGAGGAUUGCUUGAGGCCAGGAGUUCAAGACCAGCAACACAGUGAGACUCCAGUCUCUACAAAAUAAAAAUAAUUUAAAAAUGAGCCGGGCAUUGUGGCACACACCUGUAGUCCCAGCUACUCAGGAGGCUGAGGUGGAAGGAUUGCUGGAGCCCAGGAGGUCCAGGCUGCGGUGAGCCAUGAUUGUGCCACUGCACUCCAGCCUGGGUAACAGAGCAAGACCCUGUCUCAAACACACAAACCAAAACCCUUCAGUUGCUUCUCAUCUCACUCCAAGUAUGAGCCCAAGUCCUUAUAAUGGUCUCCAGGGCCUUACCUGAUAUGCCUCUGCUCUCUCCUUACCUCUCUACCAUCUAUUGGACUACCCAGCCCAGAUCUCUUAGCUGAUCCUUAGAAAUGCCAAGCUUCCUUCUGCCUCAGGACCUUUGUACUUGAUAUUCCCUGUGCCUGGAAUACCCUUGCCUUAGAUAUCUAUCUGGUUUAAUCUCUCAUCUUCUUUAGGCCCUUCAGGUUAUGUGACCUCAGUGAGGCCCUCUUUGACCAUCUUAUUUAAAAUUGUAACCUCACUACAUGGCAUCCCUAGUCUUCUCUGCUUUACUGUUCUCCAUUGUACUUAUCUCUGAUUGGCAUUCUCUUCAUAGGUAUUUUCCCCAGUGUUGAGAACAGUGACUGACACAUGGUGGGCCCUUAGAACUUAUUUAUUAGUUGAGUGAAUUUAACCUGUACUCACAGAGAUGCAUAUUUGGGACAAUGAGACCUGUAGCCCAAAUUAUGAGGACUUAAUAUUUCAAGAUGAUUUUACAAGAUGAAUUAAUUAAAUUUAUUUAUAUCCUGCCUUGUUCUAAAAAAUAUUUUAAAAUGCAUAUAGUAUGUAGGAUGGGGACAUAAAGAGAAUAAGACAAAGCAAAUGUAAUAGUAUUAAAGUGGGUAAAGUUAAUGUACAGAAGGUCCUGCACAGUGGCUAAAGUCAUGUUAUAAAUUUGACUUAUUAGAGAGUUAGGUUGCUCAGAAAUGAUUGAACUGGAAUCAAGAAUUUGUUCUCUGGCACAGGUCACAGAUAUUUGAGUCUUACAUAGAAACCCAGAAAACCUAUUUAACUAUAAGACAUUGUGCAGUUACUCUUCUAAAAAAAAACUUGCUUUCUGUAUUAGGAAAUUUCCUAUUGGCAUAAAAUGUACACAGUCUGUCCAUUACAAAGGCUCUGCUACAUUUGAGAGAUGGUAGUCACAGCUACUACCUCUGCUUAUGUCAUGUCCAGGACAUUCCCAAGGUUGAUUUAAACCUAGUAAUUGGAUAUUUUUGAAAGCUGUGAAAAAUACCAACCAGCACAUCAAUUACCCCAGUUUCUCCUCCUCUAAUCAUGAGGUAGCAUGAGAGUCCAGUGGUUGUGGCUUCCUUCCUUUUGAGGUAGAUAAUUGGCAACUUAGAAAUAGGUUAUUGGCUGGGCGCAGUGACUCACACCUGUAAUCCCAGCAUUUUGGGAGGACAAGGCAGGCAGAUCACCUGAGGUCAGGAGUUCGAGACCAGCCUGGCCAACAUGGUGAAACCCUGUCUCUACUAAUAAUACAAAAAUCAGCCAGGUGUGGUGGCACAUGCCUGUAAUCCCAGCUACUCGGGAGACUGAGGUGGGAGAAUCUCUUGAACCCAGGAGGCGGAGGUUGCAAUGAGCUGAGACCGUGCCACUGCACUCCAGUCUGGGCAACACAGUGAGACUCCGUCUCAAAAAAAAAAAAAAAGAAAAGAAAAGAAAAAGAAACAGGUUCUUAUGUAGUCACAACUAAACAGGGUAGGAAGAUUGGGAGUUAGAUGAAUUAGACUUCAAGAAAUUUUUCACCAAUACAGUAACCAAAAUAAGAGCUACUCUCUCUCUCUCUCUCUGUGUGCAUACAAUUAAUAGAUAUUGUACAGUACAUGUCUUUCUGUUCAUGGUAUGUAUAGUUUCCUAAUUCUGUCUUUUUUUUUUUUUGUCUUUUAAAACUGAGUCUGAGAAUUAUUGCCAUGUCUGCAGGCCAGAGAUAAAGCAGGGAACGUGGCGACGGACUACAGGCCUUUCAGUAAACUCUGCAGUACCUCACUAAACAAAGCUGGUAUUUUUGAGGCAAAAGAUAAGAAUAUUUAGCUAAAUGGUGUUCCACUUGCAAAAUGUGCUAGUUCUUAUUUGAUUUUUUUCUUCUUUCUUAGAAAGCUUUCUCUUUUCUAUCUUUUACUUAGAGAUAAAUAUUACAUUUGAAGUCACAUCUGUCCCACACCAUUUUUUUCAGGGUUGAAAGAGGAAAACUAAAUGAACCAUAGACUUAGGGAAAUAAUGGAAAUAUGUAUGUUUUAAAAAAACCAUUUAUGUUCCACGUAUUUCAAGGAAAGGAAAUGAGGAGAAACAUUAAGAACACCACAGAACCAUUAAAAUGGACAACUCAAAGGGAAAGUAUUUUACCAAAAGCAUUAUGUAUAACAUGUUGCUGAUUAAAUUUGUGUUGUUAUAUUUAAUGUGUAAGUAUACAUUAUCCUAACUAAUUUAAAAUAUGUUUAUUGAAUUUACUUUACAUAUUUUAUUUAUUUGAUGGAACUUUAUGUUCAUUUUUUAAGAAGUCAAGUAUCUCCUCAUUUUGGCAUUUGAUGAGUAACGGGAGAAAACCUGAGAAGAGACAGAAGUAAUGCAAAGGUCACCGUAUCUUCCAGCAUAAGUGAUGUAGAAACAGAAAGAUCUUAUUUUCAGUCAAAGUGGUGAAGUGGCAGAAAGAAAAUAUCCCCCAACUGGUUUGCUGACACUAAUUUUGCCAUAUAGUGAGGACAAAAAAAACAUGUCUAGGCGUUUAACUCAUUAUCUCCUAAACUAUGGUACACAGAAUGUCUGACACAACUGCAAGAGAUUUUGUAAGCCAAAAGGGUUCUGUAAUGACAUGUUUGGAAAAUGUUGCAGUCUUUUUUGAAAGUUUAUAGUGUAUCUUAACACGUUCCAAACGUGUAAUCACAAUUCUUUUUCGCUCAUAAAAUCUAUUAAUAACCCUUGGAAUCAUCUUUCAGGAAAUGCUGAAAAUUUUGCUUCUGUUUAGGAUGUAGAAUGUUGCAAGAGAACAUUGUUCCCAUCAUAACAAUGAGAAAAAUCUUGAUAAUCCACAAAGUCAUGAUGCUUCUUGAGCUCAUCAGAGAGUUGAGGUCACAAGGCAAUCAGAUGAACUGAAAUUCCAAAGAGAGGCAAGCCCUUUUGAAGAGAGACAGGACACAGAAACUGUGUUACCUUUGGCAGAGCAUAGGAGGAAGAGAAGGCACCGUAAAGGUUUUGGAGCCCUCUCUUAAGUCAGAACUCUGUCCCAAAAAUCUUCUGAGUGUCAUCUCAGGACUUUGGUUAUACUCAUGGCACGAUGGCCAACUUUCAGGAGCACCUGAGCUGCUCCUCUUCUCCACACUUACCCUUCAGUGAAAGCAAAACCUUCAAUGGACUACAAGAUGAGCUCACAGCUAUGGGGAACCACCCUUCUCCCAAGCUGCUCGAGGACCAGCAGGAAAAGGGGAUGGUACGAACAGAGCUAAUCGAGAGCGUGCACAGCCCCGUCACCACAACAGUGUUGACGAGCGUAAGUGAGGAUUCCAGGGACCAGUUUGAGAACAGCGUUCUUCAGCUAAGGGAACACGAUGAAUCAGAGACGGCGGUGUCUCAGGGGAACAGCAACACGGUGGACGGAGAGAGCACAAGCGGAACUGAAGACAUAAAGAUUCAGUUCAGCAGGUCAGGCAGUGGCAGUGGUGGGUUUCUUGAAGGACUAUUUGGAUGCUUAAGGCCUGUAUGGAAUAUCAUUGGGAAGGCAUAUUCCACUGAUUACAAAUUGCAGCAGCAAGAUACUUGGGAAGUGCCAUUUGAGGAGAUCUCAGAGCUGCAGUGGCUGGGUAGUGGAGCCCAAGGAGCGGUCUUCUUGGGCAAGUUCCGGGCGGAAGAGGUGGCCAUCAAGAAAGUGAGAGAACAGAAUGAGACGGAUAUCAAGCAUUUGAGGAAGUUGAAGCACCCUAACAUCAUCGCAUUCAAGGGUGUUUGUACUCAGGCCCCAUGUUAUUGUAUUAUCAUGGAAUACUGUGCCCAUGGACAACUCUACGAGGUCUUACGAGCUGGCAGGAAGAUCACACCUCGAUUGCUAGUAGACUGGUCCACAGGAAUUGCAAGUGGAAUGAAUUAUUUGCACCUCCAUAAAAUUAUUCAUCGUGAUCUCAAAUCACCUAAUGUUUUAGUGACCCACACAGAUGCGGUAAAAAUUUCAGAUUUUGGUACAUCUAAGGAACUCAGUGACAAAAGUACCAAGAUGUCAUUUGCUGGCACGGUCGCAUGGAUGGCGCCAGAGGUGAUACGGAAUGAACCUGUCUCUGAAAAAGUUGAUAUAUGGUCUUUUGGAGUGGUGCUUUGGGAGCUGCUGACAGGAGAGAUCCCUUACAAAGAUGUAGAUUCUUCAGCCAUUAUCUGGGGUGUUGGAAGCAACAGCCUCCACCUUCCAGUUCCUUCCACUUGCCCUGAUGGAUUCAAAAUCCUUAUGAAACAGACGUGGCAGAGUAAACCUCGAAACCGACCUUCUUUUCGGCAGACACUCAUGCAUUUAGACAUUGCCUCUGCAGAUGUACUUGCCACCCCACAAGAAACUUACUUCAAGUCUCAGGCUGAAUGGAGAGAAGAAGUGAAAAAACAUUUUGAGAAGAUCAAAAGUGAAGGAACUUGUAUACACCGGUUAGAUGAAGAACUGAUUCGAAGGCGCAGAGAAGAGCUCAGGCAUGCGCUGGAUAUUCGUGAACACUAUGAGCGGAAGCUUGAGCGGGCGAAUAAUUUAUACAUGGAAUUGAGUGCCAUCAUGCUGCAGCUAGAAAUGCGGGAGAAGGAGCUCAUUAAGCGUGAGCAAGCAGUGGAAAAGAAGUAUCCUGGGACCUACAAACGACACCCUGUUCGUCCUAUCAUCCAUCCCAAUGCCAUGGAGAAACUCAUGAAAAGGAAAGGAGUGCCUCACAAAUCUGGGAUGCAGACCAAACGGCCAGACUUGUUGAGAUCAGAAGGGAUCCCCACCACAGAAGUGGCUCCCACUGCAUCCCCUUUGUCCGGAAGUCCCAAAAUGUCCACUUCUAGCAGCAAGAGCCGAUAUCGAAGCAAACCACGCCACCGCCGAGGGAAUAGCAGAGGCAGCCAUAGUGACUUUGCCGCAAUCUUGAAAAACCAGCCAGCCCAGGAAAAUUCACCCCAUCCCACUUACCUGCACCAAGCUCAAUCCCAAUACCCUUCUCUUCAUCACCAUAAUUCUCUGCAGCAGCAAUACCAGCAGCCCCCUCCUGCCAUGUCCCAGAGUCACCAUCCCAGACUCAAUAUGCACGGACAGGACAUAGCAACCUGCGCCAACAACCUGAGGUAUUUCGGCCCAGCAGCAGCCCUGCGGAGCCCACUCAGCAACCAUGCUCAGAGACAGCUGCCCGGCUCGAGCCCUGACCUCAUCUCCACAGCCAUGGCUGCAGACUGCUGGAGAAGUUCUGAGCCUGACAAGGGCCAAGCUGGUCCCUGGGGCUGUUGCCAGGCUGACGCUUAUGACCCCUGCCUUCAGUGCAGGCCAGAACAGUAUGGGUCCUUAGACAUACCCUCUGCUGAGCCAGUGGGGAGGAGCCCUGACCUUUCCAAGUCACCAGCACAUAAUCCUCUCUUGGAAAACGCCCAGAGUUCUGAGAAAACGGAAGAAAAUGAAUUCAGCGGCUGUAGGUCUGAGUCAUCCCUCGGCACCUCUCAUCUCGGCACCCCUCCAGCGCUACCUCGAAAAACAAGGCCUCUGCAGAAGAGUGGAGAUGACUCCUCAGAAGAGGAAGAAGGGGAAGUAGAUAGUGAAGUUGAAUUUCCACGAAGACAGAGGCCCCAUCGCUGUAUCAGCAGCUGCCAGUCAUAUUCAACCUUUAGCUCUGAGAAUUUCUCUGUGUCUGAUGGAGAAGAGGGAAAUACCAGUGACCACUCAAACAGUCCUGAUGAGUUAGCUGAUAAACUUGAAGACCGCUUGGCAGAGAAGCUAGACGACCUGCUGUCCCAGACGCCAGAGAUUCCCAUUGACAUAUCCUCACACUCGGAUGGGCUCUCUGACAAGGAGUGUGCCGUGCGCCGUGUGAAGACUCAGAUGUCUCUGGGCAAGCUGUGUGUGGAGGAACGUGGCUAUGAGAACCCCAUGCAGUUUGAAGAAUCGGACUGUGACUCUUCAGAUGGGGAGUGUUCUGAUGCCACAGUUAGGACCAAUAAACACUACAGCUCUGCUACCUGGUAAUGAAGGAAUACACAUCCUGAAGAUCUCGUGACUAUACUGGCAUUUCAGAUCCACCCCACCCCCAGACUCAUCCCACUCUCUCCCAGCAUUUUGUCUGGGAAGAGAGACUACCCCAUCUUUACCACCCCCUAGAAAUGAGCUGCAAUAACAGGAACAUGAGACUUCGCAAAUCUCUGGAAAAUAAUAUCCAAAUGAAAUUAAGUCUCACUGAACAUUUCAAUCAAGAAUGGCAGGGAUCUAUUUUAUUGAAUAUUCUAGCUACUGUAACAUUGAUAUUUAUUUUUGUUUGACAUUUUAACACUUUGUACUGCAAAGAGUGAACUAUAUAUGAGAUAGAGAGACAAUAAUUUCUUGCAAAAAAAAAAAGAGAUAAAAGAAAGAACAGAAAAAAAGAAAUAAGUGGAAUUUAAGAGCAACAUCCUUGGGAAUUUGUGGGGCCGGGAGGUAUUAUUGCUGCUUGAACAGGGGACCAGGUCUUUUGGCCAUAAGUGACUAAAGAAGAGCCAGAGCAAGACAUUGAACAUUUUAGAACACAAAGAACAGCAAAAGAAAAGCAAUUCCAGGCAACUUGUGAACAGACCAUAUUCACUUCAACCAGCUUGUCCAGGUGGCUUACGGAAAUGACCUAGAAAAGUCUGGUGACCAGAUACUUGCACCCAAUGUCUUCAAGGGCAUGUGCUUCCUCUAGGAGGGAAAAACAGACAAACAAACAAACAAACAAACCUGUGUAUGUGGAAGCUGGUUUCAUUUUUAAAUGUUUAAGCAGCAGUUGGUAGUGAGGUUUACAGAUAGUGUCAAAUCUUGUUUUUGGCAAAUACGUCCCUUUUUAGUGCUGUCACUGUCAUUACCUUGGCAAAUGUGCUACCUUGACCCAACGUGUUGAUCUUUCAUACUCAAGUGCCAUUUCCUUGUAGCUCAUUUCCUUUCUGCCUGCUGACCACUUCCUGUAGGAACAAAGGUUGGGGGGCAGUACUGAGGAGGAGAAAAGGGUGAGAGAGGAAGAACAUCUACAGUGGUGUUAGGAAAACGAACGUGGAAUUUAUAAAACUCCAUUCUCAGGAUCACUCAGUUCAGCUACGAGGAGAAGAUGGAACCACCCCUCUCUGGAGCCAGGUUGCUUGUCUACUUGAGUCAUAUUGAUUCAAGCAGGAGAACAGACUUUGAAGGCAGCUAGGAUGUAUGUGUGUCUAUACAAUGUCUGAGCCCAAACCAUCCCUUUGUUUUUAUUCAAUAACUCAUUCUAUCUUAGAAGUUCUUUUUUUUUUUUUUUUUUUUGACAGAGUUUUGCUCUUUUUGCCCAGGCUAGAGUGCAAUGGCACAAUCUCAGUUCACUGCAACCUCCAUCUCCCAGGUUCAAGCGAUUCUCCUGCCUCAGCCUCCCGAGUAGCUGGGAUUACAGGCGCCCGCAACCACGCCUGGCUAAUUUUGUAUUUUUAGUAGACACGGGGUUUCACCAUGUUGGCCAGGCUUGUCUCAAACUCCUGACCUCAGGUGAUCCGCCUGCCUCGGCCUCCCAAAGUGCUGGGAUUACAGGCAUCAGCCACUGUGCCCGGCCUAUCUUAGAAGUCUUAAUGACUGGCUACCACUGUCAGAAUAAAAGCAAAAACAAGCAGCUUGCAAAAGGCAACUCCUCUCCCAGCACAAUAGCAUUUUUGUUCAAUGCUACUUGUAAAAUAUCUUUUACUUCACUCCAAAUCAAUGCAGUUUUAAAUAACUGGAUUUGAACAUUUGUGGAAAGAACAAGGGAUGCUGAGCAGGGAUAGGAAGGAUUUUUACAUUGCCAAAAGCAUGAGGUCCUGCCUGUCUCCAGGGUCAUGGGCUCUGAAAAGCAUUCCAAGGUACUUCAUGGUGCCUUGGCCUUAAGGAAAAAUUUUUUUAGAAUUUUAUGUACAAAUAGGUGUUGACCUAGUACCUGUCCCUGUCUCCAAGACAGAUUACCGUCAAACAACCUCUCUAGAUUCACUGGACUCUUUGACACUGCAUCAUGUUGGACGUUAGGAAAUACUUGCACAGACAGCUGUUAAACCAUUUCCAAUGCACAUGAAAAUGUUGCCGCUCCUCUGGGUUUUACUGAUUGCAUCAGCCAAAAAGGAAAGGCAGGAGGGAAUUUAGAGUUCCUUUUGCUUGUUUGAUCCAUUUGUUUACACUUUAUGUUGAUACAUUGAUUUAAAAUGUAGUGUCUGUGAUUUAUAGCUCUUAGGAUGAAGGAAAAUGUUUAAUUUAUACAAAGAGCAGUAUUGUUUGCAUUAAUUUAUUCCAUUUUGUAAAAAUUCUGUAGCUGGACUACAUGAAAGAUCUUAAGUUAUGGCAUUAUUAUCAUUGUUAUUUUAUUUUAUAAUAUUAUCAUUCUCAUUUUCUGUCGAUCAGAAGGUGUGAUUUAUGAUGUGGCACAAUGGUUGUGUUUAUUGCUAACCAGGAAUUAUUAUGGAUUUUAUGAUUUUAAUGAAGGAAUGAAAAUGGAAUUCCCAUUUGGGAGCUCCCUGGUAUUGAUCUUAGCUGUGUUCCCUAAUUUUCUGUGUACAACAAUCAUCUGAGGACGCAUGUUCUGCCCUGAAGCCCAAUGGAUACAUUGUGAUUUUGACUUGAUCAUGAAAGCUCCUGGGUGGGCCGAUGACCCCCAGGAUGUCAAAUAGUGGAUGGACAUAUAGUUAAAAAGCUGUAAACUUUCUAAAGUUUCUUAGGAAAUAAAUUCAUGGGACUAUAUUAGAAAUAAAAAGAGAAUGAUUUAAUGUCCUGAGAGGAACAGACCUAGAGGGUUUCCGCACAGGGCUCAUGGAUUCGUUUCAAGAAUUGACAACAUAGUUUGCAAUCUCCUUCCUGCCAGACCCCUUUGUUCUCCCACCUUUAUUCUCCUAGUGGAGAGUAGCAGGGAGACUAAAAAAAGAAAUGGUAUACAGUAGUCCCCUCUUACCCAUGGCUUCAUUUUCAUGGUUUCAGUUACGCUCAACAGCAGUCCAAAAAUAUUUGAUGGAACAUUCCAGAAAUAAACAAUUCAUAAAUUUUAAUUGCACAGCAUUCUGAGGAGCAUGAUGAGAUCUUGCCCCUUGCUGCCCUGGAGGUGAUCCUCCCUCUGUCCAGCAUAUUCAUGCUGCUCAUCCAUUAGUCACUUAGUAGCAGUCUCGGUGAUCAGAUCGACUGUCUCGGUUAUCAGAUGACUGUAUCGCAGUGCUUGUGUUCAAGUACCCCUAUUUAAUUAAUAAUAGCCCCAAAGGGCAAGAGUGCUGUGCCUAAUUUACAAAUUAAAUUUUAUCAUAGAUAUGUAAGUAUAGAAAAAAAAACAUAGUAUAUAUAGGGUUUGGUACUAUCAGAGUUUUUAGGCAUCCACUGGGGGUCUUGGAAUGUAUCCCCCAGAAAUAAGGGAGGACUACCGUAUAUACAUGUAGGGCAUGACAUAAAAUGCCUAACUGUGAUGUCAUCCUAGAACAAGACUAAAGAACUUUAAGAAGGAGGCCUGGUCACUUAGAGGACCAACGACUGGAAAAAAAUUCUUGAAAGGCUAUAUUUUCCAUCCUCUUGACUUCAGAUCUCACUGUACUGUAAAUCUCUCUGGUUCAUUAUUCCUUGGAACAGAGAUGCUACAACUCUAUGUCUUCUUUCUAUCCAACAUAAAACACUGGCAGUUUUGUCCAAUUCUUGCCCACCUUUAGUGGCAACAGAGAAACAUGAGGGUCAGCUUUUAUCUUACAUCUUUCAGUGAUGGUCUUCCUAGAAAACCUACCCCUGAUACCUCGUAAUUUUGAUCAGUUUUUUUUGAAUUCUCAUCUUGAUUAUCUGUUAUGCUAUUGUCAUCAUACACCUUAUGUGGAUUAACUGUUAUGAGUAUGUUAGGGUAGUACGUAGUGGCUGAAUCUCAGUCAUUCAUUGUAUAGUCGAGAGUUGAAUAAAGUCCAUAUUGAACACAUUUUUUUAAGUAGAAUUGACUAGAGGUUUCAGAGGAGAAUAAGGUCCUUAGUGGAGGUUAAAAAGGGAAAUACCUUCUCUAGCCCAGCCUGGUCCUUCGCUGCCUGCCUUGUGAUAACCGGGAAAAUCUUGAAUUGAUGUAUGUUUCUUUGAGAACGACUCCACAGUCAUCUGAAGAGUGUUGAAUCAAGAGCUCAGGGAAGUUAUGAGCUAAUUCUUCAGUCCUGACAAGUGUGUUACAACAGUGCUUCCAGGAACCUCACAAGACUGUGAUUUCAAGCUGCUUCAUUGAUGGAAAGUUUCACCAUCUUGGGAUGAAUGUCCAUGUUCCGUUAGCGUCUGUUUUUAACUGACUGCAAGAUGAUGAGUUUUAAUUUGGGUUGCAGAUGAGCAUUUGGUUCUGAUUUUCAUCUAUUUCAAGAUCAUAUCCUCUGGAUAACAGUUCCUUUUAAAAUUGCUUUGCAGAGGGGCUGAGAAGCCUGCAUCUACUUUGAAAUUAUAAUGGACCUUACCACCACUUAAGUUUAGACCUGUUUGCAAGAUGGUGGGGAGCUCCUACUGAGAAAGAUGAAGAUGCUAGCUCUAUUGUAAACUGGCGUCUUCAUCUAGCUACUUGAAGUUGAGAUACUAUAUUUUAAAAUGUUGGCAUCAAACAAAUCUAUCCUUCUAGAAGUAAAGACAUUUUGAGUAGGAUUUAGUAAGUACUGGACAUCUCCUGUAGAGCUUCAUCAUGCUAAAUUAUUCCCCUCUCCUUUUCUAAAUAAUAGAUGUGCUUGGGUUUGGGAUUUACCUGGCACCAACCCAGACUUUUUUUGGGGGGGGGUGAGGGCGCAGGAUCUCACUCUGUCACCAGGUUGGAGUACAGUGGCAUGAUUAUGGCUCACUGCAGCCUCAACCUCCUGGGCUCAAGUGAUCCUCCCACCUCAGCCUCCUGAGUAGCUGGGACCACAGGUGUGUGCCACCAUGCACAACAAUUUUUUUUUUUUUUUUGUAGAGAUGGGCGUCUCCCUGUGUUGCCCAGGCUGGUAUCGAACUCUGGGCUCUAGCGAUCCUCCUGCUUUGGCCUCCCAAAGUACUGGGAUUACAAACGUGAGCUGCCAUGCCCAGCCUCCAGACUAUUUUAAAUGCCCUCUCCCACUGUGGAACAUUGGCAUCCUUUAAGAAUAAAUGCAUCCUUUUUGAUCAAAUGAUUUACUCUUUUUUUCUUCAAUGUCCUCAUGUCUCAAUUUUUUUUUCCUUUUCUUAAAACAGUCCCACUUGAACUUCCUGGAACUGAAUUCUCCAGAACAUAAUAUUUAUAAUCCAUAGAAUUCCUGCCCUGCUCUGCAGUAGAGUGUGCUAUGUUUUGUUUUCCCACUGAGCCAGAAGCCGAAAUAUUAUACUACCACUUACCACCAUCUACCACCUCCAAGACCAAGACCAACAUUAUGUAUUGAGCAUCGUAUCUUUCCUACUGAGCCUAGACACAGCCUCAGAACCUCUCAACAUAGCACUUGGAGCAACAAUUGCCGCUUGAUUGGAAUUGCCAUUUGAGCUUGAGUUAGCCCCAAUGGCAGAACGACAGGCUCGCACUAGUGUCCACCUGUGGCUGUCAGGGGCGGUACCACAGAAAGGGGAAAGGCCACUUGCCUCUACCCACUGCCCUUUUGGACAACAAUUCCAAUUGAAGGAACACCAAUCACUGAUGGAUCCCAUUCCAAAAUGUCUCUUCAUUCACAUCAUUUAAUUCUGUUGAAUGAAUAUGUUCCUCCCUCACCUUUUAUAAACAGAAAAUUAAUAUAAGUCCCAGUUACUUGCUUCUUAGACUCUGUGAGACUCAUGUACCAAAACAAUGUGACAUUCUUUUCGAGACUUUGACUUGUACGGUCAGUAUGAAUUUAGUGCCUUUCCAGGCAGCAAAAUGUUUCUUCUUUGCUGAUUUCAUAGGACAAAUAUCCUAGCAUACUCACACCACCAGUGUCCCACCCUCACAGACUGGCACAUUAGAAUCAUAUUAAUCUGCUUGUUUGCAUGUUACAACUGAUACUGCAAAAGCCUAUUCAAGUCGGACUGAACUAGGCUAAGCAGAGGACCCUUGUGGAACCUGGAGCAUUUCUCAGGGACAGGUGGCUAAAGAGGGGAGCUCUAAAAUCACUGCUCUGAGAAACAGGAGGUGGGUUAAGGCUUUUGUUAACUGUCAUGUGGCCAGGGUACGAUGGCAGGACUUCACAGAGCAGAGCCCUAAGCAGAUGGCAAGGCCACUGUAAGGAAGCUCCCGGCAGCAUCCCAGGUCUGCUCUCCAGAGCCACUUCACAGCACUCAGGGAUCGCUGGCUCCCGGCCCUAGGCUGCUGUCCAGUGACCAGGUGGACAGGGUCCUCCAGUGACUGCAGGCCAAGGGAACCCCAGCCAGCAUGUGCAAGCUAUUAGGAAGAUGUCCCAUCUUGCCCAUAUCACCCCAGUGGCUCUUCACCUUCAGAGUGACCACUUCCCAGACUCUGGAAGUGGGAAGACCCUCUUUGACGCUUUAUUACAGUAAUUUGAGCUCCUAUCGACUUGGAGCGAAUGAAUUUCUCUUUUGUGGUUAGGUCUCCAAAUGAACCUCCUUACCUGGCUCCCCUCUGGUCUCCUGUACUGUCAGUCCCCAGCUCCCAGUGUUGUUUUCUGAUGCCGGCUCCCUCUCUGUAUUGAACGGCAAUGGGAACAAGAAUGACUAUCAAAGCAAACAAAUGCAUGGAAUUAAACAAAAAGUGUACUUCA